AGGGCGGAGCGGGCGGCAGACCCGGAGCAGCAUGUGGACUCUCGGGCGCCGCGCAGUAGCCGGCCUCCUGGCGUCACCCAGCCCAGCCCAGGCCCAGACCCUCACCCGGGUCCCGCGGCCGGCAGAGUUGGCCCCACUCUGCGGCCGCCGUGGCCUGCGCACCGACAUCGAUGCGACCUGCACGCCCCGCCGCGCAAGUUCGAACCAACGUGGCCUCAACCAGAUUUGGAAUGUCAAAAAGCAGAGUGUCUAUUUGAUGAAUUUGAGGAAAUCUGGAACUUUGGGCCACCCAGGCUCUCUAGAUGAGACCACCUAUGAAAGACUAGCAGAGGAAACGCUGGACUCUUUAGCAGAGUUUUUUGAAGACCUUGCAGACAAGCCAUACACGUUUGAGGACUAUGAUGUCUCCUUUGGGAGUGGUGUCUUAACUGUCAAACUGGGUGGAGAUCUAGGAACCUAUGUGAUCAACAAGCAGACGCCAAACAAGCAAAUCUGGCUAUCUUCUCCAUCCAGGUAUGUAGUGGACCUAAGCGUUAUGACUGGACUGGGAAAAACUGGGUGUACUCCCACGACGGCGUGUCCCUCCAUGAGCUGCUGGCCGCAGAGCUCACUAAAGCCUUAAAAACCAAACUGGACUUGUCUUCCUUGGCCUAUUCCGGAAAAGAUGCUUGAUGCCCAGCCCCGUUUUAAGGACAUUAAAAGCUAUCAGGCCAAGACCCCAGCUUCAUUAUGCAGCUGAGGUCUGUUUUUUGUUGUUGUUGUUGUUUAUUUUUUUUAUUCCUGCUUUUGAGGACAGUUGGGCUAUGUGUCACAGCUCUGUAGAAAGAAUGUGUUGCCUCCUACCUUGCCCCCAAGUUCUGAUUUUUAAUUUCUAUGGAAGAUUUUUUGGAUUGUCGGAUUUCCUCCCUCACAUGAUACCCCUUAUCUUUUAUAAUGUCUUAUGCCUAUACCUGAAUAUAACAACCUUUAAAAAAGCAAAAUAAUAAGAAGGAAAAAUUCCAGGAGGGAAAAUGAAUUGUCUUCACUCUUCAUUCUUUGAAGGAUUUACUGCAAGAAGUACAUGAAGAGCAGCUGGUCAACCUGCUCACUGUUCUAUCUCCAAAUGAGACACAUUAAAGGGUAGCCUACAAAUGUUUUCAGGCUUCUUUCAAAGUGUAAGCACUUCUGAGCUCUUUAGCAUUGAAGUGUCGAAAGCAACUCACACGGGAAGAUCAUUUCUUAUUUGUGCUCUGUGACUGCCAAGGUGUGGCCUGCACUGGGUUGUCCAGGGAGACCUAGUGCUGUUUCUCCCACAUAUUCACAUACGUGUCUGUGUGUAUAUAUAUUUUUUCAAUUUAAAGGUUAGUAUGGAAUCAGCUGCUACAAGAAUGCAAAAAAUCUUCCAAAGACAAGAAAAGAGGAAAAAAAGCCGUUUUCAUGAGCUGAGUGAUGUAGCGUAACAAACAAAAUCAUGGAGCUGAGGAGGUGCCUUGUAAACAUGAAGGGGCAGAUAAAGGAAGGAGAUACUCAUGUUGAUAAAGAGAGCCCUGGUCCUAGACAUAGUUCAGCCACAAAGUAGUUGUCCCUUUGUGGACAAGUUUCCCAAAUUCCCUGGACCUCUGCUUCCCCAUCUGUUAAAUGAGAGAAUAGAGUAUGGUUGAUUCCCAGCAUUCAGUGGUCCUGUCAAGCAACCUAACAGGCUAGUUCUAAUUCCCUAUUGGGUAGAUGAGGGGAUGACAAAGAACAGUUUUUAAGCUAUAUAGGAAACAUUGUUAUUGGUGUUGCCCUAUCGUGAUUUCAGUUGAAUUCAUGUGAAAAUAAUAGCCAUCCUUGGCCUGGCGCGGUGGCUCACACCUGUAAUCCCAGCACUUUUGGAGGCCAAGGUGGGUGGAUCACCUGAGGUCAGGAGUUCAAGACCAGCCUGGCCAACAUGAUGAAACCCCGUCUCUACUAAAAAUACAAAAAAUUAGCCGGGCAUGAUGGCAGGUGCCUGUAAUCCCAGCUACUUGGGAGGCUGAAGCGGAAGAAUCGCUUGAACCCAGAGGUGGAGGUUGCAGUGAGCCGAGAUCGUGCCAUUGCACUGUAACCUGGGUGACUGAGCAAAACUCUGUCUCAAAAUAAUAAUAACAAUAUAAUAAUAAUAAUAGCCAUCCUUUAUUGUACCCUUACUGGGUUAAUCGUAUUAUACCACAUUACCUCAUUUUAAUUUUUACUGACCUGCACUUUAUACAAAGCAACAAGCCUCCAGGACAUUAAAAUUCAUGCAAAGUUAUGCUCAUGUUAUAUUAUUUUCUUACUUAAAGAAGGAUUUAUUAGUGGCUGGGCAUGGUGGCGUGCACCUGUAAUCCCAGGUACUCAGGAGGCUGAGACGGGAGAAUUGCUUGACCCCAGGCGGAGGAGGUUACAGUGAGUCGAGAUCGUACCUGAGCGACAGAGCGAGACUCCGUCUCAAAAAAAAAAAAAAGGAGGGUUUAUUAAUGAGAAGUUUGUAUUAAUAUGUAGCAAAGGCUUUUCCAAUGGGUGAAUAAAAACACAUUCCAUUAAGUCAAGCUGGGAGCAGUGGCAUAUACCUAUAGUCCCAGCUGCACAGGAGGCUGAGACAGGAGGAUUGCUUGAAGCCAGGAAUUGGAGAUCAGCCUGGGCAACACAGCAAGAUCCUAUCUCUUAAAAAAAGAAAAAAAAACCUAUUAAUAAUAAAACAGUAUAAACAAAAGCUAAAUAGGUAAAAUAUUUUUUCUGAAAUAAAAUUAUUUUUUGAGUCUGAUGGAAAUGUUUAAGUGCAGUAGGCCAGUGCCAGUGAGAAAAUAAAUAACAUCAUACAUGUUUGUAUGUGUUUGCAUCUUGCUUCUACUGAAAGUUUCAGUGCACCCCACUUACUUAGAACUCGGUGACAUGAUGUACUCCUUUAUCUGGGACACAGCACAAAAGAGGUAUGCAGUGGGGCUGCUCUGACAUGAAAGUGGAAGUUAAGGAAUCUGGGCUCUUAUGGGGUCCUUGUGGGCCAGCCCUUCAGGCCUAUUUUACUUUCAUUUUACAUAUAGCUCUAAUUGGUUUGAUUAUCUCGUUCCCAAGGCAGUGGGAGAUCCCCAUUUAAGGAAAGAAAAGGGGCCUGGCACAGUGGCUCAUGCCUGUAAUCCCAGCACUUUGGGAGGCUGAGGCAAGUGUAUCACCUGAGGUCAGGAGUUCAAGACCAGCCUGGCCAACAUGGCAAAAUCCCGUCUCUACUAAAAAUAUUAAAAAAUUGGCUGGGCGUGGUGGUUCGUGCCUAUAAUUUCAGCUACUCAGGAGGCUGAGGCAGGAGAAUCGCUGUAACCUGGGGGGUGGAGGUUGCAGUGAGACGAGAUCAUGCCACUUCACUCCAGCCUGGCCAACAGAGCCAUACUCCGUCUCAAAUAAAUAAAUAAAUAAAUAAAGGGACUUCAAACACAUGAACAGCAGCCAGGGGAAGAAUCAAAAUCAUAUUCUGUCAAGCAAACUGGAAAAGUACCACUGUGUGUACCAAUAGCCUCCCCACCACAGACCCUGGGAGCAUCGCCUCAUUUAUGGUGUGGUCCAGUCAUCCAUGUGAAGGAUGAGUUUCCAGGAAAAGGUUAUUAAAUAUUCACUGUAACAUACUGGAGGAGGUGAGGAAUUGCAUAAUACAAUCUUAGAAAACUUUUUUUUCCCCUUUCUAUUUUUUGAGACAGGAUCUCACUUUGGCACUCAGGCUGGAGGACAGUGGUACAAUCAAAGCUCAUGGCAGCCUCGACCUCCCUGGGCUUGGGCAAUCCUCCCACAGGUGUGCACCUCCAUAGCUGGCUAAUUUGUGUAUUUUUUGUAGAGAUGGGGUUUCACCAUGUUGCCCAGGCUGGUCUCUAACACUUAGGCUCAAGUGAUCCACCUGCCUCGUCCUCCCAAGAUGCUGGGAUUACAGGUGUGUGCCACAGGUGUUCAUCAGAAAGCUUUUUCUAUUAUUUUUACCUUCUUGAGUGGGUAGAACCUCAGCCACAUAGAAAAUAAAAUGUUCUGGCAUGACUUAUUUAGCUCUCUGGAAUUACAAAGAAGGAAUGAGGUGUGUAAAAGAGAACCUGGGUUUUUGAAUCACAAAUUUAGAAUUUAAUCGAAACUCUGCCUCUUACUUGUUUGUAGACACUGACAGUGGCCUCAUGUUUUUUUUUUUUUUAAUCUAUAAAAUGGAGAUAUCUAACAUGUUGAGCCUGGGCCCACAGGCAAAGCACAAUCCUGAUGUGAGAAGUACUCAGUUCAUGACAACUGUUGUUCUCACAUGCAUAGCAUAAUUUCAUAUUCACAUUGGAGGACUUCUCCCAAAAUAUGGAUGACGUUCCCUACUCAACCUUGAACUUAAUCAAAAUACUCAGUUUACUUAACUUCGUAUUAGAUUCUGAUUCCCUGGAACCAUUUAUCGUGUGCCUUACCAUGCUUAUAUUUUACUUGAUCUUUUGCAUACCUUCUAAAACUAUUUUAGCCAAUUUAAAAUUUGACAGUUUGCAUUAAAUUAUAGGUUUACAAUAUGCUUUAUCCAGCUAUACCUGCCCCAAAUUCUGACAGAUGCUUUUGCCACCUCUAAAGGAAGACCCAUGUUCAUAGUGAUGGAGUUUGUGUGGACUAACCAUGCAAGGUUGCCAAGGAAAAAUCGCUUUACGCUUCCAAGGUACACACUAAGAUGAAAGUAAUUUUAGUCCGUGUCCAGUUGGAUUCUUGGCACAUAGUUAUCUUCUGCUAGAACAAACUAAAACAGCUACAUGCCAGCAAGGGAGAAAGGGGAAGGAGGGGCAAAGUUUUGAAAUUUCAUGUAAAUUUAUGCUGUUCAAAACGACGAGUUCAUGACUUUGUGUAUAGAGUAAGAAAUGCCUUUUCUUUUUUGAGACAGAGUCUUGCUCUGUCACCCAGGCUGGAGUGCAGUGGCACGAUCUGGGCUCACUACAACCUCCGCCUCCUGGGUUCAAGCAAUUCUCUGCCUCAGCCUCCCGAGUAGCUGGGAUUACAGGUGCCUGCCACCACACCCGGCUAAUUUUUGUAUUUUUAGUAGAGACGGGGUUUCACCAUCAUGGCCAGGCUGGUCUUGAACUCCUGACCUAGUAAUCCACCUGCCUCCGCCUCCCAAAGUGCUGGGAUUACAGGCGUGAGCCACUGCACCCAGCCAGAAAUGCCUUCUAAUCUUUGGUUUAUCUUAAUUAGCCAGGACACUUGGAGUGCAUCCCGAAGUACCUGAUCAGUGGCCCCUUUGGAAUGUGUAAAACUCAGCUCACUUAUAUCCCUGCAUCCGCUACAGAGACAGAAUCCAAGCUCAUAUGUUCCAUCUUCUCUGGCUGUAUAGUUUAAGGAAUGGAAGGCACCAGAACAGAUUUAUUGAAAUGUUUAUUAGCUGAAGAUUUAUUUAGACAGUUGAGGAAAACAUCAGCACCCAGCAGUAAAAUUGGCUCUCAAAGAUUUUCUUCUCCUGUGGAAAGUCAGACCUCUGAGGCCCCAUCCAGGUAGAAGUACUAGUGCAAGAAGGGCCUCUGCUGUCCACUUGUGUUUCUGUGAUCUGUGGGAACAUUGUUAACGCCACAUCUUGACCUCAAAUUGUUUAGCUCCUGGCCAGACACGGUGGCUCACACCUGUAAUCCCAGCACUUUGAGAGGCUGAGGCAGGUGGAUCACCUGAGGUUAGGAGUUCGAGGCCAGCCUGGUCAACAUGGUAAAACCCCGCCUCUACUAAAAAUACAAAAAUUAGCUGGCCGUAGUGGCGCACGCCUGUUAUCCCAGCUACUCGGGAGGCUGAGGCAGGAGAAUUGCUUGAACCUGGGUGGUGGAGGUUGCAGUGAGCCGAGAUUACACCACUGCACUCCAGCCUGGGUGACAAGAGGGAAACUCCAUUAAAAAAAUGUAAUUCCCGUGUCUGCCAUCUUAAGUGUAAAGGUGGCUAAAUUAUAUAGAAAAAUAAGACAAUAUCAUUUCCCAAUUACAUUCCUUUCCUACCGCACUCUAUGAUGCUAGCUGAGAUUUUUCCAAAAGAAAAUGGCUUAAAUAAAACCCUAAGAGAAAGAAAAACUUUAAAUCCCUCCAAAGCUCAAAAGUAAUAGAAACAGAUGAGUUUGGAGUCAGGAUUUCUCUGUAAGAUUGCCUAGGCUGUGUACUGCACAUCUCCAGGUGCCACUGUUGACAGAGAUUAUAACUACAAUGUGAAGUGAAUGGUGCCACUGACAGUUAUGCAAACCGUCCAGAGCAUAGCCACCUGAUCCUGCUGGGAUUCCUCUUGCCAGUCCAUCAGCAGUUCCCCUUGAAAGUUUCACCAAACAUCCCUUAAAUCUGCCCUCUCCUGCCCGUCCCCAGUGGAGGUCCUCAUCAUUUUUCACCUGCAUUUUUGCAGGAGCUUUCUUAUAUCCACCUUCCUCCUUUUCUCUCAGCCCAUCAUCUAGCUACACAGUCUCCAGGGUAAGCUUUCAGAAAGGCAAUCUCUUGUCUGUAAAACCUAAGCAGGACCAAGGCCAAGUUUCUUAGCCUGAAAAAUGUGCUUUUCUGACUGAACUGUUCAGGCACUGACUCUACAUAUAAUUAUGCUUUUCUACCCCCUCACACUCAACACUUUGACUCCAGCAAUCCCAAAUCCCCAGAUCCCUAAGUGUGCUGUGCUAUUUUCACGUGGCUCUCAGACUUGGCCAGUGCUGUUUCCAUUUUGGUCUUUAUUCCCCACAUCUCUGCCUGGGGGGUAGAUUCUACCCUGAAAAAUGUUCUUGGCACAGCCUUGCAAACUCCUCCUCCACUCAGCCUCUGCCUGGAUGCCCUUGAUUGUUCCAUGUCCUCAGCAUACCAUGUUUGUCUUUCCCAGCACUGACCUACCAUGUGUCACCCCUGCUUGGCUGUACCUUCCAUGAGGCUAGGACUAUGUGUCUCCUUUGUUGACUGCUGUUGCCCUAGCAUCUUGCACAGUUCCUUGCACACAAUUAGAGCUCUAUAAAUGUCAAAUAAAUGUGUUAUAAUUAUAUGUUUAAGAUAGUUGUUCAAAUAAACUCUAAAUAACCCCAA